UCACCCACCUAAGCCUCCCACAGUGUUGGGAUUAUAGGUAUGGGCCACCAUGCCUGACCCUAGAGACUAUUUUUAAUACUAGUUUUAGGUUCUCAGAAAAAUGGAGAAGAUAGAGAUUUCCCAUAUCCCUCUGACCCCAUACAUGCAUAAGCUCCCCAUGAUCAAUAUCCCCCCCCAAAGUUGUACAUUUGUUAGAACUGAUGAACCUAUGUUGACAUUAUCGUCAUUGGAUUCUCAUUAUCAUCCAAAGUCCAUAUUUUACAUUAGGGUUCACUCUUGGUGCUUUACAUUCUAUGGGUUCAGACAAGUAUAUAAUAACAUGUAUUCACCAUUAUAGUAUCAUAUGGAGUAUUUUCACUGCCCUAAAAAUCCUUCCGGGCUUUGCCUGUUCAUUCCUCUCUUACUCCUAAUUCCUGGCAACCACUGAUACUUUUGCCUUUUCUAGAAUAUCAUAUAUUUAGAAUCAUACAGUAGAUAGCCUUUUCAGAUAGACUUCUUUCACUUAGUAAUAUGCACUUAAGUUUUCUCCAGGUCUUUUUUUGGCUUGAUAGCUCAUUUCUUUUUAGUGCUGAAUCAUAUUUCAUUAUCUUAAUGAACCACAGUUUAUUUAGCCAUUCACCUACAGAAGGACAUUUGGUUGCUUCCAAGUUUUGGCAAUUAUGGAUAAAGCUGCUAUCAACAUCCAUAUACAGGUUUUCAUGUAGACGUAAGUUUUCAACUCCUUUGUGUAAAUACCAAAGAGUGUGUUUGCUGGGUUAUAUGGCAAAAACAUGUUUGCUUUUGUAAGAAACCAACAAAAUGUCUUCCAAAGUGGCUGUAUGAUUUUGCAUUCCCACCAGCUGUCACUGCUAAUUGGGCAGACCUCCUUUAGAGAUGUCGCCAAAGAUAGUGUAAUGCUCUUCACUGUAGGCAUUUAUGAUCUAUACAAGAAUAACAGUGGAUUCUGGGUCAGUGCCUUUAUUUUAUCCUGCCAAGUUCAAGAGAAAGGUUUUUUCUUAUUCUAAGAGAAGACUGUUAUGGUAAAGUAAAAGGAAGAAAUAUAUAAUUACUCUUCUAUUGAGGAGGGAGAAGAAGGACACACUGUGAUGUAAAUGGCAGAAAUUCAAUAAUUUAAUUCAAACUAAAGAGAACGGGAAUGUAUUGAAUUCAGGAAUGGAAUGUAACGGGAAACUCCACUGGUGGUCUUCAGGCAUGGCUGAAUCCCGUGUCUCAAAUGAUAUCUUCAGGAAUAUGUUCCUCCCAUCCCUCAGCUCUGUGUUCCUUGGUGUGGUCUUUACUUUUUCCACUUGGUAAUAUGAAUGUCCUCCAAUAUCCUCCCCUACUGCCAGAGAUACCAAGAAAGGAGAGCUUCUCUGAUAGUUCCAUCAAAACUCCCAGGGAUGACUCUGAUUGGUCAGCCUGCAUCACAUGCCAAUUUUCUCGGUCAAGGAAGUGGGACCAUGUGAUUGACAUGAGUAUAAGACAAUCUGUUCCUGAAAGAAAAGGGUGCUGGGGGAAAAGGCAACAGAUGUCCACCACAGCAUGUUUUUUCACUUUACUGGUUAUUAUCUCUUUUUAGACUCCCUCAGCACUGGACAGCUGAGACCACGAAGGACUUGGGACCCUUUCUAGUACUUUUCUCAGGAGAUGAAUUAAGCUCUAUAGCCACAAAGUUUCCUGAGAUCCUUCUGCAAGCAGCUUCCAAGAUGGCCAGGACCCUGCCCCCUAAAUAAUUCCUCUGGGCUGUCUUUCAGUCUGUUCGGAACAGCAGUGAUAAGAUCCCCAGCUCUGACCCUAUGCCUGGUUGCCAUGGAGUCGUGGCCCCCUCUUCUGAUGACAUCUUCAAGUUGGCCGAAGCCAACGCCUGCUGGGCCCUGGAGGACCUGCGGUGCAUGGAGGAAGACACAUUCAUCAGGACCGUGGAACUGCUGGGAGCUGUCCAGGGUUUCAGCCGGCCUCAGCUGAUGACCCUGAAGGAGAAAGCAAUACAGGUUUGGGACAUGCCAUCUUACUGGAGAGAACACCAUAUCGUCUCCCUGGGGCGCAUUGCUCUGGCUCUUAAUGAGAGUGAGCUGGAGCAGCUGGACCUCAGCUCCAUAGACACUGUGGCUUCCCUAAGCUGGCAAACAGAAUGGACCCCGGGACAGGCUGAAUCCAUUUUGCAAGGGUACCUGGAUGAUUCAGGAUACAGUAUCCAGGACCUGAAGAGCUUUCAUUUGGUAGGACUUGGUGCAACCCUGUGUGCUAUAAACAUCACUGAAAUCCCACUUAUAAAGAUCUCAGAAUUCAGGGUGGUAGUGGCCAGAAUUGGGACCCUGCUCUGCAGCACACAUGUCUUAGCCGAGUUUAAGAGGAAGGCUGAAGUUGUGUUUGGGGAUCCCACUGAGUGGACCAGUUCUGUCUUGCAGGAGCUUGGGACCAUUGCAGCUGGAUUAACUAAGGCAGAGCUCCGGAUGCUUGACAAGGAUUUGAUGCCAUAUUUCCAGCCAUCAGCAAUAAAAUGCCUUCCUGAUGAGAUAUUCAAAGAGCUGUCCGCGGAGCAGAUCGCCUCCCUGGGUCCGGAGAACGCCGCGGCGGUGACCCACGCCCAGCGCCGGCGGCUCAGUCCACUGCAGCUGCAGAGCCUCCAGCAGGCGCUAGAUGGCGCCAAGACUCACUCCUGGCAGGACGCGCCCGCUAGCGCCGGUCCCACUAGAACCUCAUCCUCGCGUUCUCCCGCAGGAGCUCUCCAGUCGUGGGGUCUUUGGCUUGGUUGUCCCCUGCUGGUUCUAAUGGCCAAGCUCCUGUGGUGUCUUCCAUUUCCUUGGGACUCAGCUGAAUGGAUGGCUGUGAAGUUAUCAUUAAACUCUCAAAAUAUUCCCUGUUUUUGGUGGAGAUGGUGGUGGCUCUUCUGGUUUUAAGUUGCUCUGGGCUUUGGGGAAUUGGUUGAAAUAAAAAAUAAAAGUACAUUGGGUAAGUCAGUCACUGAUGUGAUCCUGGCGGGCUGAGAAAACUCCACCCACUGGCUCGAUCCUGCUAGAAUGAAGUUACUUCCGGGAAUUGCCAGGAUGCUUUUAGCCUUAGGUUUAGGAAGUCAGGGCUCAGGGAAGGGGGGCAGCAGUGGUGUUUGCAAACACCUUCUCGAAGACAGCAUCACAGCUGCUUGUCAGGGCGUUUCCCUGGUGGCAUCCUAGGUGCUUCUGUUCUGCCAUCAGCACACCUUGGGUUCUCCUCCUAGUCACCUAUCCACAGUAGACAUCUCAUCUGGAGGUAAGAAAACUGCAUGUUUCCGAAAAUCUUGGUGUCCCUAAAAGGCGGUGGAUUUUACAAAGCGUCAUGAGUAGGUGUUGCAGAGGCUGGAGUGUAUUUUCAGAGGUCACGUGGUUUUAUAGAAAACUAAGACUGCAGUGUGAAAGGUGUGAUCCUGUGAUCCUGCACGUGUUAUUUAAUGUCUGACUUGGUUUUCCUUCAUCCUGGCAGGGAAGUAGCAGCAAAUGGGUGCUCCUCAGGUACAGAACAUUAAUUUUUUUUGUUUUUGUUUUUGAGAUGGAGC